GGAGUUUCAAGCAGCCGCGGCGGCAGCAGCAGCCCUGGACGCAGCAGCCAAGCUCUUCGCUGGCUCCCGGGGGCUCUCCCGGGUUCCUCUCAUUGCAGGCUGAAGGUAAUGAGAGGCCCUAAGAUCCCAGAGGAUGCCAUAAGAGGAAAAGUCAGGGGAGUGUUGAAGACUCUGCCUCCUACAAAUAUGCUGUGGACCUUACAAAGCAGAGACAGCACCCUUCAAGAUGCAGAGUUCAGGGAAAGCUCCUAUACAGAGGGGAGUGGGAGUCUCCGCUGAGUUUGGAAAGAUGACUGGGGUUUGAUUGACAGAGUGAACGCGGUGGGGGGCGGCGGGGGAGAUGUUUCAAGUGAAGAGGGUCUGGAAUGUGCCUAGAACAGGGAAUCUUCUGACAGGCUGAAACAGGCUGUGUAAGGGAGUGCAGGUGGCUAAAGCUGCUCAGAGAGACACAGACCAGUGCGGAAAGAAAGUUCUGAGGGUUCAUGAAGAUAUUGGACUUUAUUCUGCAUAAAUACAGAUGGUGAAGGGUGGAAGCAGUGUUUCAGAAAAGAAAAAGUGUGUAGUGCUGUGCAUGCAGCAUUGGUAGAAAUGGGCUUGAUGGGAGGAAAAUUACUUAGCGGACUAGGGCCUGAGGUCAUGGGGACCUAUGAAAAGGAAAAUAAAAUGCAUGAGGGUGGCUAUAUGAUUAUGUGCAGAGGGGGUGGAAACUGUUGCUCAAAACUGAAUCUUAAAAUUUGUUUUGUCAUUGCUUUACCCAAAAUAGUCGACCCUAGUUGGAUUUUUUUGGAGAAAAUAUUUUGUCCCUUUUAAAAAGGUUCUAGUAAGAAGCAGCUUUAAUGCUGUUUGUGGAAGGAAAAAGUUACAAGGAGAAAGAGUGAAUACAGUGCAUGAUUAAAGGAGUGAUGGAAAGUGACAAUGGCUUUCAAAAGAGCACAGGCGAAUUGACACGUAUUAUGACAAACACGAUCUUACAGUGACUUCAUUUUCUUGUGAGUGUUGGGAAAUACUUUCUAGAUAUUCUAAUAAUGAUGCCGUUAGCAUUGUACAAUUUUUAAUUAAAAAGCUUAUAACACAAAUAGAAACUUAAAUCUGGAGGAGAACUUCAAUAUCCUUUCAUCAUUUUACAGAGGAGCUAACAAGACUAGAGAGUAAACAACUCACCCACAGUCACCCAGCAGGUGUGUGACAGGUCCAUUGCCAGAAGGAUUGUUGGAGUACAAAAUGACAGUAUGAGCAAGUAAAAUGGUAUGCCUAGUACCAGUGAGAGCCCUCAGUAAACAGUAGGCAGCAACCAAGCUGGUGGGAAGCCUCCUAUCCAGGAGGAUGCAAAUUGUUGACUUGCAAGAUGAUGAGGAUUUCCAGAUAGACACAGUCUAUUCCUGCAGUGAUGGUGUCAUACCAGCCCAUGGAACAGUGCCCAUCAAACAAGAUGCCACCGGAAAUGUCAUCUUCUCCCCAGACGCUGGCUUGCAAGCACAGCAGCACCCAGAGGCUAACCUAUUUCCCCUAUAGCCCAAGCUCUGAGAUCUCCCGUCUGGUCACAAUGAUCUACAGGAGAGGAAGAAAGCUAUCUAGGGACGAGAUCUAGAAUCAACUGAGAGAGAUGCUUAAAAAUCACCAGUUACUUUAAUGACAAGAAACUAGAAUGUGUUUAAUGCUAAAAAGAAGGAUCCAGGCCAAGGAGGGUAAAGAAAAUGCAGAAUGCAAAUUAUCCCCUCACUGGGGGAUAUCCGGGAGCGAAGUCCCUGAGCUGCUGAGGAAGCUUUACGCCUAAGGAGAAGAGGAAACUGGUUCAGAACUGUGGGCAGCCAGCCCAAGAGCACGCAGCUGUCCAGGGGCAGAGUCCACGUCUGGCUUCUUUGUCUGGAGUUGAAAGCCAGAUCACCACCUUCUGCCAUCCGCAGAGCCAUCCUGUGCAAAGGAAGGAGCUAGGCUGUGCGCCCUGGGCGUCAUGAUCCUUCUGCGGGCCUCCGAAGUGCGGCAGCUGCUUCACAAUAAGUUCGUGGUCAUCCUGGGGGACUCUGUGCAUAGGGCAGUAUACAAGGACCUGGUGCUUCUGCUGCAGAAGGACCGCCUGCUCACUCCCGGGCAGCUUAGAGCAAGGGGGGAGCUGAACUUCGAACAAGAUGAGCUGGUGGACGGAGGCCAGCGGGGCCACAUGCACAACGGCCUUAACUACCGUGAGGUCCGCGAGUUCCGCUCCGACCACCAUCUGGUACGUUUUUACUUCCUCACCCGCGUGUACUCCGAUUACCUCCAGACCAUCUUGAAAGAGCUGCAGUCGGGCGAGCACGCCCCCGACCUGGUCAUCAUGAAUUCCUGCCUCUGGGACAUCUCCAGGUAUGGUCCGAACUCCUGGAGAAGCUACCUGGAGAACCUGGAGAACCUGUUCCAGUGCCUGGGCCAGGUGCUGCCCGAGUCUUGCCUCCUGGUGUGGAACACGGCCAUGCCUGUGGGCGAGGAAGUCACCGGGGGUUUUCUUCCGCCCAAGCUCCGGCGGCAGAAGGCCACCUUCCUGAAAAACGAAGUGGUCAAAGCCAACUUCCACAGCGCCACCGAGGCACGUAAACAUAACUUCGAUGUACUGGACUUGCAUUUCCACUUCCGCCACGCGAGGGAGAACCUGCACUGGGACGGGGUGCACUGGAAUGGACGUGUGCACCGCUGCCUCUCCCAGCUGCUGCUGGCCCACGUGGCCGACGCCUGGGGUGUGGAGCUGCCCCACCGCCACCCCGUGGGCGAGUGGAUCAAGAAGAAAAAACCUGGCCCGAGAGUCGAAGGGCCGCCCCAGGCCAACAGAAAUCACCCGGCCUUACCUCUGUCCCCACCCUUACCUUCCCCCACAUACCGCCCCCUGCUUGGGUUCCCACCCCAGCGCUUGCCGCUGCUCCCGCUCCUGUCCCCACAGCCUCCUCCUCCCAUUCUCCAUCACCAGGGAAUGCCCCGGUUCCCACAGGGUCCCCCAGAUGCCUGUUUUUCCUCAGACCAUACUUUCCAGUCGGAUCAAUUCUAUUGCCAUUCAGAUGUCCCCUCAUCAGCCCAUGCAGGUUUCUUCGUCGAAGACAAUUUUAUGGUUGGUCCUCAGCUGCCUAUGCCCUUCUUCCCCACACCCCGUUAUCAGCGGCCUGCCCCAGUGGUACAUAGGGGUUUUGGCAGGUAUCGUCCCCGUGGCCCCUAUACGCCCUGGGGACAGCGGCCUCGACCUUCAAAGAGAAGGGCCCCAGCCAAUCCUGAGCCAAGGCCUCAAUAGACGGACCUAGGCCUUAUUUCCUCUUUAUGAACAUGGAUUGGACAGAUCUGACACUUCCUUUCCAUUGCUUGGCCUGAACAGACUGACCUUGUUAACUUAAGCCUGGAGUCCAUGCCUCGUCUUCCUUUUGUUCAUUGCUGUUACCAAGAAAGCCAAGGAAGAGCAGCCUGACUCAUUCUUCUUGGCUGCAGCCUCUUCCCCACUUCCUGGGAGUGACCCAGCGUUAUUCCUGCCUCCUCACUCCUAUUCUCUUUGCCUUUGUGUAAAAAUAAAAUGGAAAUAAACAAGUUGCACAGAA